GGAAACAUUGCUCUGCGAGUCCUCCCGUUUAAACGCAUUCAAUUUUUGGGUCUCUCUCUCUCUCUCUCUCUCUCUUCUUCUCUUCUCUCUCUCUCUCUCUCUCCUCUCUCUCUCUCCUCUUUCUCCCCCCUCUCUCCCUCCUCUCCUCUCUCUCUCCUCUCUUCUCUGAACCUCUCUUCUCUUUCUCUUUUCUUACAUAUUCUACUAGUUGUUUUCCCCUUCUUCUUCUCCUUUCUCUCCUUUUUCUCCCUCCUCCUUGUCUCUUUUACUCCAUUCCUGCAGAAGAGAGAGGGCUAAACUUAAAGAAAAAAAAAAGGAGGAGGAGGAGGAGGAGGCACCCCCUUCGUAUUCUUCUUAUCGUUAUUUUAUACAUAUAUGAUUUUUUUUGGAGGGAGGGUGUUGGUUGCCGGCUGAAGAGCACUUAUUUAAAAUACUAAAAAAAGAACAUUUUUGGGCGAUCUCCAGGGUUUUUUUAACUAGCUCUGUGUGUUAUAGCAGAAGAAGCAGAAGAAGGAGCAAGAAAGAGGAAAAGAAGAGGAUUAUUUAUUCGACCUACUUUGGAUGUCUCUCUCGCUUUUCCUUUUUCCUUUUUUUGGCAAUUAUUUUCUUCUGAUUUUUAUUUUUUCUAUUUCGCUGUGAUUUCGUCGCCGGCGUGAAUUAUCCCGUAUUUUUCUCCCCCUUCCGUCACCUCCCGAAAGAAGAAGGCAGCGAGAGCCCGGCGCCACCGGCACAACAAAAAGAGCAAAGUGUGUGAUCUUCCUCGCCGGCUGCCUCCCGCUCUCCAGCGCUGCCUUCCUGAAUGGCUGGCUGCGUCCGGCCCUGGACCUGGCCCCCCGACACCCGCGCGCCCUGAUCGCCGGCGGCAGCCUCGCCCAGCGCCCUGCUCGGCUCACCGCGCUCCCCGCACUCCCGAGCCCGGCGAGGGCUCCCGCCGGGACAGCGGCGGCGCCGCGGGCGGCCCCGGCCUCCGCUCGCGCUCCGGCUGCGGCCCCGACUCCUGCUCGGACUCCGGCCCGGGUCCCGGCUCCUCCAGCGGCGCUCGCCGCAGCAGCUCCGGCGGCAGCUCCAGCGGCGCCUGCAGCCGCGACCUCCUCCUCCUCCGCCGCCGCCGCCGCCUCCGCCCUCGCCGGCUUCCUCUAUGUCGGCUCAGCCCGCGCGCUGCGCGUAGCCCGAGCGGCCGGCGGGCGGGCGCCCGGCGCGGGUGAGCGACUGUGUGUGCGAGUGUGUGUGUGCGCGGGGGUGCGGGCGAGGCGGAGGGCGAGUGUGUGCGCGCGCCGUGGCCCAUGCCCGCCGCCCCCGGCGCUGCGCCCCGCGCCGCUCCCGGCUGCCGCCUGUGCCAUUUCUGAUUUUGCAACUUGGGGAAGAAGAAAAAAGCGAGAGAAGGGAGCUUGCUCGCCGGGGGGUGGGGAGGGGGGAAGGAGAGCGCGGCCCCCCCAGGAACGGAGCGCGGGGGGAGCGGGCGAGGGGAGCAGGGGUGUUGGGGGGGGAGCCUGAGAGCCUGGGGGGGCUGCAAAAAGAGAGAAAGAAAACAGCAGGAACCACAACAAAACGCCAGCAGGGCGGGCGGGCGCGCAGCAGCAGCGGGGCGGCCGAGGCAGUAGCGGCGGCAGCGGCGGCGGCGGCGGAGGCAGCGGCCGGUGUCCGGCUCGGGCUCGGCUCCUGCGACCCCGGGGCGCCCGGCGGGCCCCCCGCCCCCUCCCCCUCCCCCCUUCCCCUUCCCCUUCCCCUCCCAGCGCGCCCGCGCGCCCCGCGGCCCUCGGCGAGCAGCUCGGCUCCCCCCAGCGCUCCCCGGGCCCAAAGAUAUGGCAAUGGUAGUUAGCAGCUGGCGAGAUCCGCAGGACGACGUGGCCGGGGGCAACCCCGGCGGCCCCAACCCCGCAGCGCAGGCGGCCCGCGGCGGCGGCGGCGGCGCCGGCGAGCAGCAGCAGCAGGCGGGCUCGGGCGCGCCGCACACGCCGCAGACCCCGGGCCAGCCCGGAGCGCCCGCCACCCCCGGCACGGCGGGGGACAAGGGCCAGGGCCCGCCCGGUUCGGGCCAGAGCCAGCAGCACAUCGAGUGCGUGGUGUGCGGGGACAAGUCGAGCGGCAAGCACUACGGCCAAUUCACCUGCGAGGGCUGCAAAAGUUUCUUCAAGAGGAGCGUCCGCAGGAACUUAACUUACACAUGCCGUGCCAACAGGAACUGUCCCAUCGACCAGCACCACCGCAACCAGUGCCAAUACUGCCGCCUCAAGAAGUGCCUCAAAGUGGGCAUGAGGCGGGAAGCGGUUCAGCGAGGAAGAAUGCCUCCAACCCAGCCCAAUCCAGGCCAGUACGCACUCACCAACGGGGACCCCCUCAACGGCCACUGCUACCUGUCCGGCUACAUCUCGCUGCUGCUGCGCGCCGAGCCCUACCCCACGUCGCGCUACGGCAGCCAGUGCAUGCAGCCCAACAACAUUAUGGGCAUCGAGAACAUCUGCGAGCUGGCCGCGCGCCUGCUCUUCAGCGCCGUCGAGUGGGCCCGCAACAUCCCCUUCUUCCCGGAUCUGCAGAUCACCGACCAGGUGUCCCUGCUACGCCUCACCUGGAGCGAGCUGUUCGUGCUCAACGCGGCCCAGUGCUCUAUGCCGCUGCACGUGGCGCCGUUGCUGGCCGCCGCCGGCCUGCAUGCCUCGCCCAUGUCUGCCGACCGCGUCGUGGCCUUCAUGGACCACAUCCGCAUCUUCCAGGAGCAGGUGGAGAAGCUCAAGGCGCUACACGUCGACUCAGCCGAGUACAGCUGCCUCAAAGCCAUCGUGCUGUUCACGUCAGACGCCUGUGGCCUGUCGGAUGCGGCCCACAUCGAGAGCCUGCAGGAGAAGUCGCAGUGCGCACUGGAGGAGUACGUGAGGAGCCAGUACCCCAACCAGCCCAGCCGUUUUGGCAAACUGCUGCUGCGACUGCCCUCGCUGCGCACCGUGUCCUCCUCCGUCAUCGAGCAGCUCUUCUUCGUCCGUUUGGUAGGUAAAACCCCCAUCGAAACUCUCAUCCGCGAUAUGUUACUGUCUGGGAGCAGCUUCAACUGGCCUUACAUGUCCAUCCAGUGCUCCUAGACCUUGGGCGCUUCCCACCUGCCCCGUCCCCCUAGAGACUCAGAGGACCCACCUGGGCCAAGGACUCCAAAGCCGCGGGGACACCGGGAAGUGCAGCGGGCCAGGCAGGCUGGGUGGGAGGGAGGAGGGCCGAGACAGGAGCAGCCCACCCAGCAGAAAUACAAUCCGAGCUACAAAGCAUGGGAAAAAGAGACUCUUUUAGGAUCAGAUCUGUGAGCACGUUGGCGAGGAAAAACAAAACAAACAAAAAAAAGAACCUUGUGUCUGUCUGGUGAAAAAAAGAAAAACAAAUUGGAAGAGAGGACCAUGAGAAUUUUAAUAAAACAGAAGGAAACUAAUGGACCUUCCAGGAUUUAUUGUGGACGGAUGUGGAUAUAUUCUGUACAGGAACAACACAUAUGGAAGUGGACUGAAGCCUAUGUAGAAACACACACACACUGAACAUUGUUAUUCAUUUUGUAAAAUACUAGUCUUUAUUUUCAUUUUUUGUAAAAUUUAAACAUCGUAUGCGCAUAAAGAAAAAGGAAACAAGAAUUAGGGGAAAAUAACAUUUUCCAAAUAAUUAUAAAAAAUUGUCCUGUGUCUAUGUAUCUAUAUCUGUUUUGUAUUUUUUUCUGGUUCCAAACCAGAUUUCCUGUGAUUCUAUACUAAUAAUUUUUGAUAUAACCCUUUGCUUCUUAUAAUGAGUGCGAUAUAUGUUGUCGAGGCUGUUCUUCAAGAAUUAAAAUUGAAGUGAAAAUUUAAACAAAAAUAAAAGAAUUUAGCAAAA